AGAGCUGGAGCCGGAGCCGGGCGGGCGCCAUGGAGGGGCUGCGGCGGGGGCUGUCGCGCUGGAAGCGCUACCACAUCAAGGUGCACCUGGCGGACGAGGCGCUGCUGCUACCGCUGACCGUGCGGCCGCGGGACACGCUCAGCGACCUGCGCGCCCAGCUGGUGGGCCAGGGCGUGAGCUCCUGGAAGCGCGCCUUCUACUACAACGCGCGGCGGCUGGACGACCACCAGACGGUGCGCGACGCGCGCCUGCAGGACGGCUCGGUGCUGCUGCUCGUCAGCGACCCCAGGUAGUCUGGGUUGGAGGAGGCAGAGCCAUGACCAAGGGGACCUGGGUACUGGCUGAAGGAAUAGGCUGGGGUAGAGGGCACUUUUGGAAGGCACUUCUCCUGCCUCCCGGGAGCCUAGAUCUCACUCCAGGGUCUGGGCUCCCAGGUGGACCAUGAAACCCUGGCCUGACCAGCUGAUGCACACUGCUUCAGACACUCCUGCUGGAGCCCCAGUCCCUGACAAGGACCUAGGACAUUUUUGCUCCUGCCCAGCCUAUCGGGAGGGAGCCUUGAGCCUUUCAGCUCUGCUGUGUGACUUUGAGGUUGUUGCUCCCCUCUUGGGGCCCUGGGUGCCCUGUCUUCAGUGGAAAGCACUGUGCCACCUUGGAAAGCUCCCAUGGGCAGCCAGAGGGCAUCGCAAGAAGAGAAGCACAGAAGGGGCAGGAGAGACACUCAGAGGCACUUCCGCUCUUGCCCAGGACAUUUUCCCAGCCACACCUUUGCCCAAGCCGUGCCCCCUGCCUGGAGCACUUUUCAACCUCUUCUCUGCAGCUCCAAUACACCUGGGAUUGCAGUCUCCUCCAGGAAGUCUUCUCAGAUUCCCUCCUUCCCAGCCAGAGAGCACCUAGCCUUCUUUGGGGCCCCCACAGGCCCUUUGUGCAGUGAACAGCCCUGGCUGGGGGUGCAGCCAGUCGUGUCCGAACUCUCCAAUGACUAAGCGGGGAGAUGCGGACAUCCUAGCUCCUUCUCAGGCCUCCAACUGUGCCCCAUUUCCACCCCCAAAUACCUCCCCAGGAGGCACCUGUGCCCACCCCCUGGGCUGUUUCCCCCUUCCCCUUAAAUCCGGAUGCCUCGUCUUGCAUAGGGUCUUGGGGCAGCGGGGAAGGGGUUCUGAAGAACUCUGGCCAAGAGGACGAGGAUCUGGGGGUGGGGAACUGGGCCUAGCUGUGGGAGGUCAUCGCGGGGCAUUGCAGGGAGUGCGUUGUGGGAAUUCCGGGUGGAGACCCUCAGGGCAGUGUGCCGGGCCUCCGUUGCACCUCUGACCUGCAGCCACGUCAUCGUUGCGCAGCCCCUGGGGAGGGUCUUUGGGGAGGGGGUGCCGAGGCUACGCAUGUCCUCGAGGGCCGUGUACACUCUCCAGGCACCAUGGGCGGAGGCGCCAGAGGCUGGGAAGAAAUAAUGUUUUAGUUAAGAGUCCUGUUGGCUGCAGGACUCAGAGCAUGGACAGGUGGAUAGUAAAUCACCACCACGGGGACAGCCGUGCCCAGACUGUGCGUUUGCUUAGCUCGGGGACAGCACUUGGCCCGGGGUCUCCUGCUCGCCUCCCUUCAGAGCAUCUGCCAAACUUCGGGCAUCUACCCUGCAAUUCCCGCUUGGCUGAGAGGAGGGGGAGAAGGAGGGGAAGAGAGAGGAGCCCCACUUCACUCCGGCAGGCAGACCUGCUGGAGCUGCUUUGCAGAAUGACUUGGGUCUUGCUGGCCCCUGGGUGUGCCUGGAGGGGGGUCUUCCUAUCCCCCUCCACCUCUCCCCUUGGUGCCUAACCCAGGACUUUGUCCCCAGAGACCCACUGUGUGCCCCCUGGAGCUCCUCCUAGAGCAGAGUCUGCUGCUGUCUGUUCUGCAGAGGGUAGCCUGAGGCCCAAGGAGGUUGUCAGGGACACACAGCAGGGGGAGGCAGCCCAGAUCCCUGCUCAUGCGUGGUUUGGGCCUCUGCUAACAGCUGGGCCACAUGCGUGUAUCUAGAGCCUGGGUCCCCUCUGUCCUCAUUUCCCUGUGCAUAUUCAGGGACAUGCCUCGUCAGGGUUUGGCAAGAAAAUGGGGCAUUUAAUAAUCUCCCCAGUUUCAUUCCUUGGUCCUUACUCCAUGCCAGGACUUGUGCACAUCUUUUUGGAGCCCUGUCUCACUUGAUUGACAGCCGGCCAGGCGCGGUGGCUCACGCCUGUAAUCCCAGCACUUUGGGAGGACGAGGCAGGCGGAUCAUGAGGUCAGGAGAUGGAGACCAUCCUGGCUAACACGGUGAAACCCCGUCUCUACUAAAAGUACAAAAAAAAUAGCCGGGCCUGGUGGCGGGCGCCUGUAGUCCCAGCUACUUGGUAGGCUGAGGCAGGAGAAUGGCGGGAACCCGGGAGGCAGAGGUUGCAGUGAGCUGAGAUCACGCCACUGCACUCCAGCCUGGGCGACAGAGCGAGACUCCGUCUCAAAAAAAAAAAAAAAAAAGAUUGACAGCCUCACUGCUCAGGGGCCAGGAUAACAGCCCAUUUUACAGAUGGCUUUUGGCUUGCCCAAGGUCACCACCCUCUGAACUGAGGCGUCCCCAACCCAUGCCGGGAGCUGGUGGAGGAAGUGGGGAAGGGUUUCCCGCUUCUCCACUGGGGGUGGAGGUGGGAGAAAGCAUUUUCAGGGUGUUUUGACAUUUAACAAACAGUAUGCAAAUCACAUGCAAAUCGCAUGCAAAUCACCACCCAUUUCUUAAGCCUCGACAGCGCUGGCAUGUUCUGAAAUAAUAAUGUUGGACCUGUCCCUUGAUGAUGACCUGGGUCGGGAGGUGCACGGCCUUUUCCUUCCUCCGUCUUCCCUUCCCUUCCCUUCCCUUCCCAUCUGUUCUCCCUUCCUUCGCCCCCUUCCUUUCCUCUCCCUCCCUAUCUUCCAUUUUUCUCUUCUUCCUUCACAUCAUUUGUCCAAGACCUCCCUGGCCUGAGAUAAACAUAAGUUGCAAAAGUGGCUUCCUGCAGCCCAUUUUCCAGGUUGGGAAACUGAGGCAUGGGCCUAAGGUCCCACAGCCACACCGAGGAAAGCAGCCCCCACUGAAUGUCACCAUGCACCAAAGUGCAUGGUCCUCGUGACACAAAGAGGGGAGAUGACAGUGGCUGGAGUUGUCAGAGCUGCUUUGAGGAAGCUCCAGGCCUGAUAGGCUUGACAGGGCCAAGGGGAACUAUUGUGGAAUGUCUUGGCCUUGAAUGACAGGCUGCUGAUUUUGGAUCUGGAGAAAGCUCACACUGACUCUUCCUGCUCCCCCAGUCUGUUUUUCUCCUGCUACUCCAUCCAUGUAUCCCUGAGUUUGGGCCACAGUCCCUCCACUUGGUUUGCAUGUCCCACCUUCUUUGUUUGGCAAGCUCCUAUUCAUCCUUCAAAGCCCUAGCUUCAAUACCUGCUACUUCAUGCAGCCAUUGCUUAUCCUUCAAGGAGAGCCUACUUCCCUCAAGGACCCUGCUGCUUCCAGUCUCACCUUCUGACUCACUCGGGAUCCACUGAACUGGGAGGUCUGUGUCUCCUCCCAGCAGAGUCAUCACUACCUUUGGGGCCGCAGGAUCACCCAGCUUGGAACUAGAUACAGAAAUGCUGUUUUGAGAGUGUACUGAAUAAAAGAUUACAUGUUUGAAAACAA